AGCGCCAACCCGCAGAACCAGGAAAGUAACGGCUACAGACAGUGAGAAAUAGUUUCGCUCGCCGGCUAGAAAAACUCUGUCGGUACCAACCCCAGAGCGUUGAGAGCAGCCCACCUCCACGCUUCCUUAACGGAGAGGUGCAGGACUCAGACUUCACCAGCCCACUCGGUCCCAGCCUUGUACGCAAAGAGACGCCAAGGACGCGCUCUCCCGCGUCCAGGCAGCCCCAGCUUGCUGGCUUGCCUGCCCGCCUGCGUGCAGCACUCGGCCGGCGUGCAGCAUGACCCUGUGGAACGGCGUACUGCCUUUUUACCCCCAGCCCCGGCAUGCCGCAGGCUUCAGCGUUCCACUGCUCAUCGUUAUUCUAGUGUUUUUGGCUCUAGCAGCAAGCUUCCUGCUCAUCUUGCCGGGGAUCCGUGGCCACUCGCGCUGGUUUUGGUUGGUGAGAGUUCUUCUCAGUCUGUUCAUAGGCGCAGAAAUUGUGGCUGUGCACUUCAGUGCAGAAUGGUUCGUGGGUACAGUGAACACCAACACAUCCUACAAAGCCUUCAGCGCAGCGCGCGUUACAGCCCGUGUCCGUCUGCUCGUGGGCCUGGAGGGCAUUAAUAUUACACUCACAGUUGCGAGGUCUCCGACCGCGGGCAGCCCCAUGAGCCCGCCUCACCCCACAGGGACCCCAGUGCAUCAGCUGAACGAGACCAUUGACUACAACGAGCAGUUCACCUGGCGUCUGAAAGAGAAUUACGCCGCGGAGUACGCGAACGCACUGGAGAAGGGGCUGCCGGACCCAGUGCUCUACCUGGCGGAGAAGUUCACACCGAGUAGCCCUUGCGGCCUGUACCACCAGUACCACCUGGCGGGACACUACGCCUCGGCCACGCUAUGGGUGGCGUUCUGCUUCUGGCUCCUCUCCAACGUGCUGCUCUCCACGCCGGCCCCGCUCUACGGAGGCCUGGCACUGCUGACCACCGGAGCCUUCGCGCUCUUCGGGGUCUUCGCCUUGGCCUCCAUCUCUAGCGUGCCGCUCUGCCCGCUCCGCCUAGGCUCCUCCGCGCUCACCACUCAGUACGGCGCCGCCUUCUGGGUCACGCUGGCAACCGGCGUCCUGUGCCUCUUCCUCGGAGGGGCCGUGGUGAGUCUCCAGUAUGUUCGGCCCAGCGCUCUUCGCACCCUUCUGGACCAAAGCGCCAAGGACUGCAGCCAGGAGAGAGGGGGCUCACCUCUUAUCCUCGGCGACCCACUGCACAAGCAGGCCGCUCUCCCAGACUUAAAAUGUAUCACCACUAACCUGUGAGGGGGACCCAAUCUGGACUCCUUCCCCGCCUUGGGACAUCGCAGGCCGGGAAGCAGUGCCCGCCAGGCCUGGGCCAGGAGAGCUCCAGGAAGGGCACUGAGCGCUGCUGGCGCGAGGCCUCGGACAUCCGCAGGCACCAGGGAAAGUCUCCUGGGGCGAUCUGUAAAUAAACCUUUUUUUCUUUUGUUUUUUAAAAACUGUUUUUCCCAUUAAUUUUCAUGGCUUCUCCGCGCCGGGGUCGCACGUCCUCAUGAGCUUCGCUGGGCUGGAGACAGCCUAGUACACUCUCCGCAGUGCUGUGAAACCUGAUUCUCUGCGUCGACUCCAGAGUAAUAGGGGCGCCCUCUAGUGAGGCCGGAGGGACCCUACCAGAGCUAGCAUCUUUCUGAACCACCCCAGGGGGACGUUAGGUGGCAGUGAUGAGGCAGGUCACCCACUCCCCCGUCCUGGAUGCCACUCAGCUAGCCCAGCUGAGUGGGGUGGGAAGGAAUAGCGUUUUGGAGUUGAUUCCC